AAAUGUUUUCCUGCGUUGCCAGGACCGUCCGCCGCUCUGAGUCAUGUGCGAGUGGGAAGUCGCACUGACACUGAGCCGGGCCAGAGGGAGAGGAGCCGAGCGCGGCGCGGGGCCGAGGGACUCGCAGUGUGUGUAGAGAGCCGGGCUCCUGCGGAUGGGGGCUGCCCCCGGGGCCUGAGCCCGCCUGCCCGCCCACCGCCCCGCCCCGCCCCUGCCACCCCUGCCGCCCGGUUCCCAUUAGCCUGUCCGCCUCUGCGGGACCAUGGAGUGGUAGCCGAGGAGGAAGCAUGCUGGCCGUCGGCUGCGCGCUGCUGGCUGCCCUGCUGGCCGCGCCGGGAGCGGCGCUGGCCCCAAGGCGCUGCCCUGCGCAGGAGGUGGCGAGAGGCGUGCUGACCAGUCUGCCAGGAGACAGCGUGACUCUGACCUGCCCGGGGGUAGAGCCGGAAGACAAUGCCACUGUUCACUGGGUGCUCAGGAAGCCGGCUGCAGGCUCCCACCCCAGCAGAUGGGCUGGCAUGGGAAGGAGGCUGCUGCUGAGGUCGGUGCAGCUCCACGACUCUGGAAACUAUUCAUGCUACCGGGCCGGCCGCCCAGCUGGGACUGUGCACUUGCUGGUGGAUGUUCCCCCCGAGGAGCCCCAGCUCUCCUGCUUCCGGAAGAGCCCCCUCAGCAAUGUUGUUUGUGAGUGGGGUCCUCGGAGCACCCCAUCCCUGACGACAAAGGCUGUGCUCUUGGUGAGGAAGUUUCAGAACAGUCCGGCCGAAGACUUCCAGGAGCCGUGCCAGUAUUCCCAGGAGUCCCAGAAGUUCUCCUGCCAGUUAGCAGUCCCGGAGGGAGACAGCUCUUUCUACAUAGUGUCCAUGUGCGUCGCCAGUAGUGUCGGGAGCAAGUUCAGCAAAACUCAAACCUUUCAGGGUUGUGGAAUCUUGCAGCCUGAUCCGCCUGCCAACAUCACAGUCACUGCCGUGGCCAGAAACCCCCGCUGGCUCAGUGUCACCUGGCAAGACCCCCACUCCUGGAACUCAUCUUUCUACAGACUACGGUUUGAGCUCAGAUAUCGGGCUGAACGGUCAAAGACAUUCACAACAUGGAUGGUCAAGGACCUCCAGCAUCACUGUGUCAUCCACGACGCCUGGAGCGGCCUGAGGCACGUGGUGCAGCUUCGUGCCCAGGAGGAGUUCGGGCAAGGCGAGUGGAGCGAGUGGAGCCCGGAGGCCAUGGGCACGCCUUGGACAGGCUUCUCUCCACAGACCAUCCCGGGUGGCAUUUGGGACCCAGCUGGAGAAUCCAGGAGUCCUCCAGCUGAGAACGAGGUGUCCACCCCCAUGCAGGCACUUACUACUAAUAAAGACGAUGAUAAUAUUCUCUUCAGAGAUUCUGCAAAUGCGACAAGCCUCCCAGGAACUGCCAUCAAGGAGGUCCCCAAAGCCUUCCGUUUGUUGUACCCUCUUUGUGCCUUGUGGGAGCAGGUGGAAUGUCACCAGAAAAGCCACUCUGAAAUGCAAGAUUCUUCUUCAGUACCACUGCCCACAUUCCUGGUUGCUGGAGGGAGCCUGGCCUUCGGAACGCUCCUCUGCAUUGCCAUUGUUCUGAGGUUCAAGAAGACGUGGAAGCUGCGGGCUCUGAAGGAAGGCAAGACAAGCAUGCAUCCGCCGUACUCUUUGGGGCAGCUGGUCCCGGAGAGGCCUCGACCCACCCCAGUGCUUGUUCCUCUCAUCUCCCCACCGGUGUCCCCCAGCAGCCUGGGGUCUGACAAUACCUCGAGCCACAACCGACCAGAUGCCAGGGACCCACGGAGCCCUUAUGACAUCAGCAAUACAGACUACUUCUUCCCCAGAUAGCUGGCUGGGUGGCACCAGCAGCCUGGACCCUGUGGAUGAUAAAACACAAACGGGCUCAGCAAAAGAUGCUUCUCACUGCCAUGCCAGCUUAUCUCAGGGGUGUGCGGCCUUUGGCUUCACGGAAGAGCCUUGCGGAAGGUUCUACGCCAGGGGAAAAUCAGCCUGCUCCAGCUGUUCAGCUGGUUGAGGUUUCAAACCUCCCUUUCCAAAUGCCCAGCUUAAAGGGGCUAGAGUGAACUUGGGCCACUGUGAAGAGAACCAUAUCAAGACUCUUUGGACACUCACACGGACACUCAAAAGCUGGGCAGGUUGGUGGGGGCCUCGGUGUGGAGAAGCGGCUGGCAGCCCACCCCUCAACACCUCUGCACAAGCUGCACCCUCAGGCAGGUGGGAUGGAUUUCCAGCCAAAGCCUCCUCCAGCCGCCAUGCUCCUGGCCCACUGCAUCGUUUCAUCUUCCAACUCAAACUCUUAAAACCCAAGUGCCUUAGCAAAUUCUGUUUUUCUAGGCCUGGGGACGGCUUUUACUUAAACCGCCAAGGCUGGGGGAAGAAGCUCUCUCCUCCCUUUCUUCCCUACAGUUGAAAAACAGCUGAGGGUGAGUGGGUGAAUAAUACAGUAUCUCAGGGCCUGGUCGUUUUCAACAGAAUUAUAAUUAGUUCCUCAUUAGCAUUUUGCUAAAUGUGAAUGAUGAUCCUAGGCAUUUGCUGAAUACAGAGGCAACUGCAUUGGCUUUGGGUUGCAGGACCUCAGGUGAGAAGCAGAGGAAGGAGAGGAGAGGGGCACAGGGUCUCUACCAUCCCCUGUAGAGUGGGAGCUGAGUGGGGGAUCACAGCCUCUGAAAACCAAUGUUCUCUCUUCUCCACCUCCCACAAAGGAGAGCUAGCAGCAGGGAGGGCUUCUGCCAUUUCUGAGAUCAAAACGGUUUUACUGCAGCUUUGUUUGUUGUCAGCUGAACCUGGGUAACUAGGGAAGAUAAUAUUAAGGAAGACAAUGUGAAAAGAAAAAUGAGCCUGGCAAGAAUGUGUUUAAACUUGGUUUUUAAAAAACUGCUGACUGUUUUCUCUUGAGAGGGUGGAAUAUCCAAUAUUCGCUGUGUCAGCAUAGAAGUAACUUACUUAGGUGUGGGGGAAGCACCAUAACUUUGUUUAGCCCAAAACCAAGUCAAGUGAAAAAGGAGGAAGAGAAAAAAUAUUUUCCUGCCAGGCAUGGUGGCCCACGCACUUCGGGAGGUCGAGGCAGGAGGAUCACUUGAGUCCAGAAGUUUGAGAUCAGCCUGGGCAAUGUGAUAAAACCCCAUCUCUACAAAAAGCAUAAAAAUUAGCCAAGUGUGGUAGAGUGUGCCUGAAGUCCCAGAUACUUGGGGGGCUGAGGUGGGAGGAUCUCUUGAGCCUGGGAGGUCAAGGCUGCAGUGAGCCGAGAUUGCACCACUGCACUCCAGCCUGGGUGACAGAGCAAGUGAGACCCUGUCUCAAAAAAAGAAAAAGAAAAAGAAAAAAUAUUUUCCCUAUUAGAGAAGAGAUUGUGGUUUCAUUCUGUAUUUUGUUUUUGUCUUAAAAAGUGGAAAAAUAGCCUGCCUCUUCUCUACUCUAGGGAAAAACCAGCGUGUGACUACUCCCCCAGGUGGUUAUGGAGAGGGUGUCCGGUCCCUGUCCCAGUGCCGAGAAGGAAGCCUCCCACGACUGCCCGGCAGGGUCCUAGAAAUUCCCCACCCUGAAAGCCCUGAGCUUUCUGCUAUCAAAGAGGUUUUAAAAAAAUCCCAUUUAAAAAAAAUCCCUUACCUCGGUGCCUUCCUCUUUUUAUUUAGUUCCUUGAGUUGAUUCAGCUCUGCAAGAAUUGAAGCAGGACUAAAUGUCUAGUUGUAACACCAUGAUUAACCACUUCAGCUGACUUUUCUGUCCGAGCUUUGAAAAUUCAGUGGUGUUAGUGGUUACCCAGUUAGCUCUCAAGUUAUCAGGGUAUUCCAGAGUGGGGAUAUGAUUUAAAUCAGCCGUGUAACCAUGGACCCAAUAUUUACCAGACCACAAAACUUUUCUAAUACUCUACCCUCUUAGAAAAACCACCACCAUCACCAGACAGGUGCGAAAGGAUGAAAGUGACCAUGUUUUGUUUACGGUUUUCCAGGUUUAAGCUGUUACUGUCUUCAGUAAGCCGUGAUUUUCAUUGCUGGGCUUGUCUGUAGAUUUUAGACCCUAUUGCUGCUUGAGGCAACUCAUCUUAGGUUGGCAAAAAGGCAGGAUGGCCGGGCGCGGUGGCUCACGCCUGUAAUCCUAGCACUUUGGGAGGCCAAGGUGGGAGGAUUGCUUGAGCUCAGGAGUUUGAGACCAACCUGGGUAACAUAGUGAGACACCAUCUCUAUUAUGAACAAUAACAGUUAAGAAAAAAAAAGGCAGGCAGGCGGUUAUGGUGGUUCCCUCCCAUCCCACCACAUAAAGUUUCUGAGACUUGAGAACAGCAAAAUGCUGUUAAAGGGAAAUAUUAAGAAUGAGAAUCUGCAGUAAGGGUGAUUCUGUGCCCACAGUUCUUCAAUUCUUUAUACCGUUUUACCCACAUGUGGUGUUACCAAAGCCGGGCAGAACCAUGCUAGCGGAAGAUGUGAAAUCCAGAUAGCUCAUUAUUGCCAAGAGCUAGGCAGCUUUGAUCUCCAAAUUGUUAUUGCUUUCAUUUUUAUUGUAAUGGAAUUGCUUUGUUUUGUUUUUUUGUUUUUGUAUUGAAGAGGGUUGUUUUCCCUUUAUUUUUCAUAAGCUAAUGUAAAUGAAGAAAAAAUGUCUUCUCUGGGCUGUAGGCCUGGCUCAGCGUACACAGGUAUACAUCCUAAGCUCUCUAUGUUCUCUAAUCUGUGGUGACUGAACAUGUGUCUCAAUGCACGGGGCAUUUCUACCUGUGUUUCUGCAGCACCCCCACUGCCUUGAGUCCCCAGCAGUGCUGUUAUUUGCCUAACACCUGUAGCCAUCUGCCACGCAGCCAGACGUGAAACGCUGAGACAGAGACCAUUUAGGUUAAAUACGACAGCUUAUCCUGCUGGGUGGGGAAAGUAAAAAAUAUGCUGGUUCAAGGCCUAAAGUAAAAUGAUCAAUAAUGUUUGUAGCAUUAAUGAAAUAUUUUCAAGAAAUGUGUCCAGGGGUAGCACUGGCUAUGUUGACGAGGCCUUUGGUAACUCAGAGAGCUCUUGGCCCUGAUGGGGACUUGCCCUUACGCUUUCUUUAUCAGGCUCUGAGUUCACACGGAGCCUCUGGCACUUCCCUGCUGUCUUGGGAGAAAGGAAACUGGUUGCCGCGGCAGGUUGUGGAAUCUGUUGCUGGAACCAGGCUGGAAGCCCACCUGGUAGUGAACAGGGCCCAGUGGGGCAGGCUGGGCAUGUUGUGGUCUAUGGGUUUGUUUCCUGGAGAAUGUUCAGGAAUGUCUUCCCAGCUGCUUUGGUGCUGAGCUCUAUUAUCUCACAGCACGUCCAGAAGGCUAACCCAGGUGGGGAGGAUGCUGACACCAGCUCCAGGUGGAGUUGGUGGUCUUAAUUUGGAGAUGCAGGGGCAACCUGUGACCCUUUGAGGCAAGAGCCCUGCACCCAGCUGUCCCGUGCAGCCGUGGGCAGGGGCUGCACACGGAGGGGCAGGCGGGCCAGUUCAGGGUCCGUGCCAGGCCCUCCUCAGUGCCCUGUGAAGGCCUCCUGUCCUCCGUGCGGCUGGGCACCAGCACCAGGGAGUUUCUAUGGCAACCUUAGUGAUUAUUAAGGAACACUGUCAGUUUUAUGAACAUAUGCUCAAAUGAAAUUCUACUUUAGGAGGAAAGGAUUGGAACAGCAUGUCACAAGGCUGUUAAUUAACAGAGAGACCUUAUUGGAUGGAGAUCACAUCUGUUAAAUAGAAUACCUCAACUCUACGUUGUUUUCUUGGAGAUAAAUAAUAGUUUCAAGUUUUUGUUUGUUUGUUUUACCUAAUUACCUGAAAGCAAAUACCAAAGGCUGAUGUCUGUAUAUGGGGCAAAGGGUCAGUAUAUUUUUCAGUGUUUUUUUUUCUACCAGCUAUUUUGCAUUUAAAGUGAACAUUGUGUUUGGAAUAAAUACUCUUAAAAAAUA